AACCCCCGAACCGCCGCGAGCUGUCCCUAGCAGUGCCUUAGCCAGGGACCUGCUUGGCCAGCGACAGAUCCUUUGCUGCUCUGUCUGCCGGUUCUUGAGGUGAAUGUCGGAAUCCAUUAUCUUUCGGGAAAGCUCUCUGGGGCAGGCAGCGCGUCAACCGCUUGUACUCUGCGAUGCCCCCGCCAGGUCUGAGCCGGACCCGCGCCCCUCCUGCGAGACACGACCCGCGCCUGCCACAGAGCUGCGGUCCUCCGGGCUCCUAGAGGGGCACUCUCCCACUUCCGGCGCGCGUGCGGCCGGGCAUUGUUCUCGCUCCCGGGGGAGCGUCCUGGGGAGUUGGAAUUCAGAAGGAAUCUCUCAGACGCAAAUCUCCAUCUCCUCCCUGCCUCACCUGGGCAGCCUUUUCAGACUGUCUCUGCCCAGAAUGUCAGGAGAGGCCACAGUCUUGGCCUACCAUGCUCCAGAAGAACAGGAAGGACUUCUAGUUGUCAAGGUUGAAGAAGAAAAUUAUGUUUUGGACCAGGACUUUGGCCUUCAGGAAAACCCCUGGAGCCAAGAGGUAUUCCGGCAGAAGUUCAGGCAGUUUAGUUACUCUGACUCCACUGGCCCUCGGGAGGCUCUGAGCCGGCUGCGAGAGCUUUGCUGUCAGUGGUUGAGGCCGGAGGUGCACUCCAAGGAGCAGAUCCUGGAGCUGCUGAUGUUGGAGCAGUUCCUGGCCAUCCUUCCUGAGGAGCUGCAAGCUUGGCUGCGAGAGCAUCGGCCAGAGAAUGGAGAGGAAGCUGUGACUAUGCUGGAGGAGCUGGAAAAAGAACUGGAGGAGCCAAGGCAACAGGACACAACUCAUGGCCAAGAAAUGUUCUGGCAGGAAAUGACAUCCACAGGAGCACUGAAGUCUCUGUCUCUGAAUAGCCCGGUGCAGCCCUUAGAGAACCAGUGCAAGACUGAGACUCAGGAGUCCCAGGCUUUCCAGGAGAGAGAUGGGGUCUCACUCUAUCACCCAGGUUGGAGUGCAGUGGUGCAACCACAGCUCACUGCAGCAGCCUUGAACCCCUGGGUUAAAGUGAUCCUCCUGCCUCAGCCUCCAGAGUAGCUAGGACUACAGUUGUACACCACCAUGCCUGGCUAAAUAUCCAUAAUAUUCAAAGCUCAGUAUUCUGUUAUUUAAUUUUGGCUUCAUUGGCAAGACAGUCCCUAAGAUGGAGAUGAAUACAUUUUCAGUAAUAGAAACCACAUAAUCAUUUGAACAGGGAAAGUUUAAUGUUAAGAAUUAUUAACUACUAAGUGUUAUAACAAAAAGUGAAACUCAAAAGAAUACAGCAAUAACAGAUAUAGAGUGUCUCUAGGGCUGAGGCAGAACAUCAAAGGUAAGAACAAAUUUGCAGGAGGGUGCCACAACUUCCCCUUUCCUGCCAGGUCUUAGAUCCAGGCCUUGUUGGAGAGGGCACAGCCACAGCCCACUGGAUGGAGAUGCCACUGCAGUGCUGAGCUGGCAGAACUCACUGAGGAGCCACACUCUGGGGUGCUAGAAGCUCCCCAUGGGGAGCUGACCUGGUACAGAACUUGCUGGGAAGCUACCCAUAGGGAUGGGGCCUUUGGAACUCAUUGGGAUGUGCACUGCUGGGUGUCCCAUGUGCUACAGAAACAAACACAAAGAACAUGCCAGAACCAGGAAGAAAAGCCCUUUCUUCCAGUUCCUCUGCAACCCCCUCUAUUGAUAAAGCUCACAGCAUGCCAGCUGGCAAAUAGUCCAGUAUCACAGACAGGGCAAUGAAGCGUAGAUUUGAAACUGAGGCAAUAAAUUGAUAGCUGUCACAGAUGCCAGGGAUUAGAACUGAAAGGACUUUGAUUAUGUUAUUGGCAAAAUCAUCCUUAUGGGCAGCAGAUAUAUCAGGUAUACCAGCUUGUUCUCAUUAAUCUUUUGUUAAAUCUGACUACCCUUCUGAUUUUGUCUUCACCAAGCAAUCUUAUUAACUUCCUAUGAAGCUUAGCUGUAAUAAGAAAAUUGCAUUUGUUCAGUCUGGUCCAUGUGAUGGUUACAUUACUCAUUAAUUCUCAUUCUGUUUUUAUUACUGAGUUUCACGGGCUUAGUUAUUAAGAGUCUACCCCAAGAGAUAAAUCUAUUUUUUGUAUGAUGAUAAAAUUAGGUAUAUGAGGACCUAAGCCCAAAGGCCAGACCCUGGACCUCGGCAGUUCACCAAAGGAAUCCAUACCAUCCAUCCACUGAAUUCUUCUGGGAAACUGCUUCCCAACCUUCCCCAGGCAUCAUACCCUGAUACUACCAUUAGCCAAGCAGGCCCUCUUAAGUAUCUUCUGCACCAAGCAGGUGCUACAUUAAAACGGGUUUUGAAAAUUCAUCUCAAGGAAAUCAAGCUGUCUCUAUUUGCAGAUAAUAUGAUCCCAUGUCUAGAAAACCCUAUCGUCUCAGCCCCAAAGCUUCUUAAGCCAAGAAGCAACUACAGCAAAGUCUCAGGAUACAAAAUUAAUGUGCAAAAAUCAUAAGCAUUCCUAUAUACAGAGAUUCCUAUAUCUCUGUGUCUGUACUGCACACCUGAACAACAAUAAGACAACCAGAGAGCCAAACAUGAUUAACUCCCAUUCACAAUUGCUACAAAGAGAAUAAAAUACCUAGGAAUACAGCUAACAAGGGAGGUGAAGGGCCUCUUCAAGGAGAACUACAAACCACUGCUCAAGGAAAUCAGAGAGGACACAAACAAAUGGAGAAACAUUCCAUGCUUAUGGAUAGGAAGAAUUAAUAUCAUGAAAAUGGCCAUACUGCCCAAAGUAAUUUAUAGAUUCAGUGUUAUUCCCAUUAAACUACCAUUGACAUUCUUCACAGAAUUAGAAAAAAAUACUUUAAAAUUCAUAUGGUACAAAAAAAAGAGCCCUUAUAGCCAAGACAAUCCUAAGCAAAAAGAACAAAGCUGGAGGCAUCAUGCCACCUGCCUUCAAUCUGUACUACAAGGCUACUAUAACCCAAACAGCAUGGUACUGGUACAAAAACAGACACAUAGACCAAUGGAACAGAAUAGAGAUCUGAGAAAUAAGACUGCACAUCUACAACCACUUGAUAUUUGACAAACCUGACACAAACAAGCAAUGGGGAAAGGAUUACCUAUUUGAUAAAUGGUGCUGGGAAAACUGGCUAGCCAUAUGCAGAAAACUGAAACUGGAUCCCUCCUUUACACCUUGUACAAAAAUAAACUCAACAUGGACUAAAGACUUAAAUGUAAAACCCAAAACUAUAAAAUCCCUAGUAAAAAAAUCUAGGUAAUACCAUUCAGGACAUAGGCAUGGGCAAAGAUUUCAUGAUGAAAAUGUCAAAAGCAAUUGCAAUAGAAGCAAAAAUUGACAAAUGGGACGUAAUUAAAGAGCUUUUGCACAGCAAAAGAACCUAUUAUAAGAGUGAACAGACAAUGUACAGAAUGGGAGAAAAUUUUUGCAAUCUAUCCAUCUGACAAAGGUCUAAUAUCCAGGAUCUACAAGAAACUUAAACAAAUUUACAAGAAAAAAACAACCCCAUUAAAAAGUGGGCAAAGGACAUGAACAGAGACCUCAAAAGAAGACAUUUAUGCACCAAAAAAUAUAUAAAAAAUAGCUCAACAUCACUGAUCAUUAGAGAAAUGCAAAUCAAGACCACAAUGAGAAACAAUCUCAUGGCAGUCAGAAUGGCGAUUAUUAAAAAGUCGAGAAACAACAGAUGCUGGCAAUGCUGUGGAGGAGUAGGAACACUUUUACAGUGUUGGUGGGAAUGUAAAUUAGUUCAACCAUUGUGGAAGACAGUGUGGUGAUUCCUCAAAGACCUAGAACCAGAAAUACCACUUGACCCAGCAAUCCCAUUACUGGGUAUAUACUGAAAGGAAUAUAAAUUAUCCUAUUAUAAAGAUAUAUGCAUGCAUAUGUUCAUUGCAGUACUACUCACAAUAGCAAAGACAUGGAUUCAACUCAAAUGCCUACCAGUGAUAGAGUGGAUAAAGAAAAUGUGGUAUGUAUACACCAUCGAAUACUAUACAGCCAUAAGCAGGAAUGAGUUCAUGUCCUUUGCAGGGACAUAGAUGGAGCCUGAAGCCAUUAUCCUCAGCAAACUAACACAGGAACAGAAAACCAAACACCACGUGUUCUCACUUAUAAGUGGGAGCUGAACAAUGAGAACACAUAGAAACAGAGAGAGGAACAACACACACUGGGGCCUGUGGGGGUGGGAGAGAAAGCAUCAGGAUAAAUAGCUAAUGCAUGUGGGGCUUAAUACCUAGGUGAUGGGUUGAUAGGUGCAGCAAACCACCAUGGCACACAUUUACCUACGUAACAAACCUGCAUGUCCUGCACAUGCAUCCUGGAACUUAAAUUAAACUUUUAAAAAAGAAAAUUCAUCUCAUCAGGUCCCCUGCCUUAAAUCAGGUAAAUGACGAAAUCAUUUAGGUAGACUAUUUUUACUUUCUUUUUUUAAAAUCUUAAGGAACAGAGACUGUGGUAAGUGUUUCUUGGGCUUUUCAUAUUGUUAUUUGUUAUGGGAUGAGUUGUGUCCCUUCAAAAUUCAUAUGUUGAAGCUGUAACCCCCAGCCAGAACCUUAGAGUAUGACUGCAUUUUUUUAGAGAUAGGGCCUUUAUAAAGGUUAAAAUGGGGUCAUUAGGGUUGGCCUUAAUCCAAAAUAAUUGAUGUCCUUAAAAGAAGAGGAGAUUAGGACACAACACAGACCAAGGGAUGAUCUUGUGAGGACCUAGCAAGAAAGUGGCCAUCUGUGGCCGGGUGCAGUGGCUUAUGCCUGUAAUGCCAGCGCUUUAAGAGGUUGAGGCAGGCAGAUUACUUGAGGUCAGGAGUUCAAGACCACUGUGAAACCCUGUCUUUACUAAAAAUACAAAAAUUAGCCAGGGAUGGUGGUGCAUGCCUAUAGCCCCAGCUACUUGGGAGGCUGAGACAGGAGGGUCACCUGAGCCCAGAAGGUGGAGGUUGCAGUGAGCUAAGAUUGCGCCACUGCACUCCAGCCUGGAUGACAGAGUGAGACUAUCUCAACAACAACAAGAAAAGAAGGUGGCCAUCAUCUGCAAGCCAAGGAGAGAGAAGAAACCAAACCUGCUGACACAUUGAUCUUGGACUUCUAGUCUCUAGAAUUGUGAGAAAAGAGAUUUCUGUUGUUUACCACCCAUUCUGUGGUAUUUUGUUGUGGAAACCCUAGUAAACAUACUAUAUUAAAA